AUGCGCUGCAGCUCUGUCCACCGCCAGUCGUGGGACAGAGUGCCGGGCUCCUCCCCUUGCAAGUCUAGCUCUUCUCCCCGCCUCCUCCGGCCUGGGGUCCGCGUGGCGGGGCGGGCGCGCACUCGGGCUUGGCGGCUGCCGGUCUCCCAGGCCGCGGCACUACAAUCGUUCAGCUAUUCUCGGAAGAGAGAAGGGAGAGGGAGGAGGCCGGGGCGGGAGUGGGGGCUGUCACCCUCGGACCCCGGCGUGAGAGGGGCCGUGCGGCCGGACGUCCUCGGGGUGGGCCCCCAGUCGGUGGCCGAAGACCUACAGCUCAGGCCCCUGGGUCCCAAAUUUCCAGGCUUUGCCCCUCCUCCUUUCUCAGAUACCCGGGUAACAGUCCUCAUAGUCCAGAUAUCCGGGACUCGGGUCCCAACCUCUCUAAACCUGGGUCUCUGUUUCAUAGAAUUUCAAAUAUCAGGUUCAGGCCCCUGCGUGCACCAGUAUCCGGGGUUCAUUCCCCGGGCGUUCAAAUAUCGGAUUCAGUCUCCAUCCCGUUCAGAUAUUCGGGGUUCAGACCCCACAAUCAGAAAUCCGGAAUUCGGCAGCUGUCGCCCUCGACGAGGGGGAGGACUGGACCGCGAGGUCAGAUUAGGUUGUCACCCCCUCCCCUCCAGGGGAGGCUUCCCGGGCCCGCCCCUCAGGAAGGGCGAAAGCCGAGGAAGAGGUGGCAAGGGGAAAGGUCUCCUUGCCCCUCUCCCUGCUUGGCAGAGCCGCUGGAGGACCCCAGGCGGAAGCGGAGGCGCUGGGGCACCAUAG